GGCCAGUCCCUGCGGGCAUCUAACUGCUAAGCCUCCGCUCAGCCAACACCCAGUUGGUCAGUCUGGUCACAGUCCAGCAAAAAGAGGGACUGCCACUCUAACCCACCAGUGACACCACUCUUCCCGGCUGGAUGGUCAAUUAGCUCUGGCAUGAGAGAAUGUCACUGCCGAGAUGCUGCCCCCACCCCCUUAGGCCCGAGGGAUCAGGAGCUAUGGGACCAGAGGCCCUGUCAUCUUUACUGCUGCUGCUCUUGGUGGCAAGUGGAGAUGCUGACAUGAAGGGACAUUUUGAUCCUGCCAAGUGCCGCUAUGCCCUGGGCAUGCAGGACCGGACCAUCCCAGACAGUGACAUCUCUGCUUCCAGCUCCUGGUCAGAUUCCACUGCCGCCCGCCACAGCAGGUUGGAGAGCAGUGACGGGGAUGGGGCCUGGUGCCCCGCAGGGUCGGUGUUUCCCAAGGAGGAGGAGUACUUGCAGGUGGAUCUACAACGACUCCACCUGGUGGCUCUGGUGGGCACCCAGGGACGGCAUGCCGGGGGCCUGGGCAAGGAGUUCUCCCGGAGCUACCGGCUGCGUUACUCCCGGGAUGGUCGCCGCUGGAUGGGCUGGAAGGACCGCUGGGGUCAGGAGGUGACUGGCAGGGAGCACCCAGAGG